GCGCCGCGUCUCCCGCGGGCAGAGAAGUAGCUGCAACUCCGCUCCCCGGCCCCAGCCGCCUCCUCCCCGCCGCCCUCCCCCGCCCCCGCCCCCUCGCUCCCUCCCGCUCUUUGUCUCCUGGGCGCCCGGCUUCUCCGCCACGCGCCCCCCACCCCGACGCCCCUUCCCCGGAGACCCCCGCGGACCCCUGCCGACGCGACGCCGCGCGAAUCGGCCCUGCCAGGCGGGGGCCCCGCGUCCGGCCAGGCCUGGCGGGCGGCAGGGGCGGGGAGGGAGGUGGCGCUCGCUCUUCGCUCUUCUCUCUCUCUCUCUCUCUGUCACACACACACACACGCACACGCACACGCACACACACACGGAGCAUCCUCCCGUCAGGUCUCCUGGUCCAGCCCCGCCCGCGCCUCCUGCUUCCAGCGAACCUGUUCCCUCUCCCCACAUCCCCCGCCCUCCAUCUCCCCCGGCUCUGGGACCCUUCCCGCCGACCUCACCCCCACCCCCGGGAUGGAGCGGCUCGAGCCCGCCCGGAGCCCCCCGCGGCCGGGGUGACGGUCCCCCCACCCCUCUCCUGCCCGGCCCCCGCCUCGAGCACCAUGGGCCUGAGGGGUUCCCGGGGCGCCAGACGCUGAAGAUGACCGAUGCCGGAGCUCUCUUGAGUCAUGGCUUCUUCAAAGCUCCGAGAACCCGUGGAUGAAGUUUUUGACCUGGACUUGGCUGUGCCAGAGACGGCCAGACUGGACAGCAGUUUACACAAGGCCCGGGCCCAACUGUUGGCCAAGGGCCGGAGACACCGGCCAUCCCGCUCCAGGCUUCGGGACAGUGCCAGCUCCGCGGAGGAUGGUGAAGGCUCGGAUGGGCCCGGAGGCAAGGUGACCGAUGGCUGCGGGAGCCCCCUGCACCGGCUGCGCUCGCCUUUGCACUCAGGCCCGGGGUCCCCGGCCGGGGGCUCUUUCUGCCUGGAUCCUCCGGGGUUGCGGCGCAGCCUGGACGAGGACGAGCCGCCGCCCUCGCCGCUCACACGCUACCGGCCCCUGCACAACGCUGCGUCGCACGAGGGCCUGGCCGCCGCCUCCUGCUCUCCGCCGCGCUCCGCGCCCUCCUCCGACAGCUCCCCCAGCUUCGUGCGCCGCCACCCGCGCGCAGAGCCGCACAGCGAAGAUGACAGCCGUGACGCCAGUCCUCCUGAGCCCGCCAGCCCCACCAUCGGCCUCGAUAAGAAGACUCGCCGAAAGUUCCUGGACCUGGGGGUCACCCUGCGCCGAGCAUCCACGGGCAAGAGCCGGAAGGAGAAAGGCAGCAACCGACUGUCCAUGGGCAGCAGGGAGUCAGUGGAGGGGUCCGGCAGGUCAGGGGGCUCCCCGUUCCUGCCUUUUUCCUGGUUCACGGACAGCGGCAAGGGCUCAGCAUCCUCGGGUAGCACCACCUCCCCCACCUGCUCCCCUAAACACGAGGGCUUCAGCCCUAAGAAGUCAGCUUCCCAGGCCCAGCUCCUGGCUCAUGCACAGGAGGCACUGAGCAACUCCUGGUGCCUAGUCCAGGACUUCGGCUCCACCCAGAUAGGGAUGGAAUCCACUCUGAGUGAUGACUCCACGCCCCCCAGCAGCAGCCCCAAGAUCCCCAGUGGGCCCUGGCAGGAGGCCAAAUGUUCUUACCCCUACCACACGCUGUCUCAGUCUUCAGAUGAGUUCCUGGAUGAACCCCUCCCCCCUGUCCACCACUGGACCAGCCAGCAGGUGGGCCAGUGGCUGCAGAGCCUCAACCUGGAACAGUAUGCUGCUGAGUUUGCUGCACGGCAGGUAGACGGGCCGCAGCUGCUGCAGCUGGACGGAAGCAAACUAAAGAGCCUGGGGCUCAGCAACUCUCAUGACCGGGCACUGGUGAAGCGCAAGUUGAAGGAGAUGGCAGCAGCUGCCGAGAAGGAGCGCAAGGCCCAGGAGAAGGCUGCGCGGCAGCGGGAGAAGCUCCGGCGCCGAGAGCAGGAGGCCAAGAAGAGCUAGGGGAGGGUGCACAGGCGCUGGCACCCGGCAGGGGCAGCCACUGGCUCCGCGGGCACAGGCCUCACCAGGGAGGCUGGACCUGGGCGCUGCACUUGGGCUAGCCUGGUCCCACGCUCUCAGGGGGGACAUGCUCUCUCUUACCCUGUCACUUGGUCUAGACCCAGAGACCCCAGAAAGGGAGACCCCAGGGAGAGGGCCUAGUAAUAAAUCCUAUUUUGAGGACUUGUUUGGCACAGAGUUCCUGGGGGAGGAGCAGAUGAAGGGGAGAGGGCAGAGAGGCCAGGGCUGAGGCAAGUCUGGGAGGCUGGGUCAGGCUGUCCCAUUGCCCUCAGGCCAUCGUGGGGCUGGGGUGGAGGGGAGCUAGGAGGCCUGCCUGCCUGCUUGCCUGCCAGAGGCCCUGAGGCCGGGCCCCAGGGCUCAGAGCUGGGCUGGGCAUUUCAGCAGGAGCCCAUGUGGGAGCGGCUCCUCUCCACUCUUCCAGGGGGCUGUGUGGUGGGAGAGCUCUGUCCUGCUCCCCCAAGAGGCCAGUGGGCGCUGCAGCAAGUCGCACUCAGGGUAGACUCCCAGCCAAACUCCUCAACAGGAGCGCAGAGAAAGCAGCCUGGGGCGAGUGCAGUCUUUGCCAGGACUCAAGAGGGGAGGAUGAACAUCCCCUUCUCCCUCUCCCCUCCUCUGUCCUGUGGGUCCCAGGGGGCGAGAUGACACCACACAGGUCUGCCUCUCAGGGCCCAUUCAAGACCUGGUCUUUGACCCAUUCUCCAAGCCAGGACUCCCUUCACUUCCUGCUGCUUCCUCAGAGGGCACCUAAGUCCUCUUUGGGAGCUGAGCAAACAGGAACUGAUAGGGACAGAGGACACCACUUCCACCAGCCAAGGCCUAGGAGCUGCUGACCUGGUCAGCCCUCACCCCAGCCAGGCAGAGAGGCAAAACCUGGGGGUCCCCGGCAGCUACGAGAUUGGAAAGGUUCAUCAGCCCUCCCCCAUCUGCCCCAGGCAUUGUCAGGGAAUCAGUGGGCUCAGAACUGGCAGGCGGUGCAAGCUCUGCUUCCCUGGGCCACACUGAGGGCUGGGGCCAGCUCCCUGGAUGGGGGUGGAGUUUACCAGCAGCCUGGGGACAGCAUGUGUCCUUUUUAGGAAAUGUCCUUGGAGGAAGUGUUCAUGUGUGGCGCUGGUCAGCAGCUAGUCCCGCUUCCAGGACACUGGUCAGAGUUACCGAUGAGGCCUGGGGGCUCCCGCUUGGAAACCCCUCCAGCUCCUCCCAUCUGCCCAGACAGAGCGGCAGAUGGCACCAAUGCAUGCUGGCUCCCUCAUUCCUGCCCAGGGGCUGUGGCUUACGGCCAGCACCCUGUACCUGGGACUCAGCCCUUAUCCCCCCUCUGCUAUCUGUGCUGGGAGAGGGGCUUCGGAGGGAAACAGAUAUGAGGACACUGGCACCAUCUGGGCCUGGUGGCAGGGCCAUGGGAGGUUGGAAGGCACCCACAUCCUUAAAGCCAUCAGUAGCUAUAGUGGGUGCCCACCUGCAUGUGAAGGGGAGGCAGUUCUCAAUUUAUUUCAAUAAAUCCUUAUGAUGUGCCAGUGACCAGAAUUUCUGUCUGCUCCAGUUGUUGGGUUGGCCGGACUCUGCUGGGCCCUGAGUAUGGUGGGACAACAGGUCUGUCACCAGGUGCUGGGCCAUCCGGCGUUCUGAACAGAUGGCUUUGCCCAGUGUUUUACUCACAGUCCUGAGCUGGGCCGGACGUCCCCGGUGCGUCAUGUGGUGGUCACAGGGCACCGCAGUGUGCGUGUGUACGUGCGCACGUGUGGGUCCCCUCCCCCAGGGAUGCAGCCAGGCCAGUCUCAUUCAGUCUCCUCUUUACUGUGGGUGUGGGUGUCACUGUCACUGCCACAGCCACUGGGAGGGACACACAGCUUUAACCCCUGUGUGCUUAGGGGAAGGGUGGGGGCAUUCAGGGUUAUAAAACUAACUAUAUACACAGAAGGUCCUAGGGAGAAAGCCACCCUGAGCACACAUGUCUGGGCACAGUGGGGGCUGGGGGCUGGAGCUCAGGCAGGAUGGACUAGGCUUGUGGAGGAGCGGGUGGGCAUGAGCAUGUGAGGACAUGCUGGGAGGGCUCAGGAGGUGGCACAGACAUUGCCAAGGCCACUGCAGGGCCUCGAGCAGCUUGGCUGGAUGGCAAGCUCUCGGUCUAACAAGGUUCUUCCACUUUAGAGUUGGGCCCUGUGAGAGCCACCCCCUCCGCCACCGACCUUCAAGCCCUGAGCGGAGGGAGAGGCUGCAGGACCAGCCUCAUUCCCCACUCACGGGUGUAACUCCUUUCCCCACUCAGUCCCCAGGUCUGGAGGGCACCCACCCUCUUCCUAACACUUCAGCAGGCCAAGGCCAGGGUGCCUUUGUGGGCUGGGGGAAUAAGGCAACGGGACAUCCACUUGGAAGGCCUGUGCUGUGGAGGGUGCUGAGGGGGACCCAGUACCCCUGGCAGAAAAGUGACAGCCCUGGUCUCAGAGAGGAGGACUGCCAUGGGAAAAUGUCUCUGGGACACCCCAUCAGGGUGGAGACAUCCCUAACCCUCAGGCAUCGCCCACAGAGAUAGGGAGGCCACCGAGGGGUCUCCACAGAGAUGGACUGGCACUUAGGGACCAUCACAGACCUAUCACCGCAGUGACUUCCAUAGAGACAGAACCUGGUCAUCAGGGAGAACCCACCCCCUGCUCCCCCAGGAGGAUGGUGAGGGGCACCACGGUGGGGGGACCCAGAGGCGGCAGUCCGUCCUCUCAGGUGCAGAUGCACGGCGGCCCUUAGCUGACGCGGUACGUGGACGUGUUCUUGGGCUCCGUGCUGGGCACACACCAGUCG